GGAAACCCCAGGGUAACUGUGGGCAGUUGGCUGAGUAGAACCAGAAGCGUAAACAUAGUCUGGCAACUGUCAAACAAACUAAAACAAACAAAAAAAAAUAUUAAAAAAAAAAGGCCCCUAGCUCAGCACUUUGAGUUUCUGUCGAACUGAAUCACCAACCUGUUGUACUCAAAGCCUAGGCGCAAGAGCGCCCGGCGCGCGGUUUCGGUCGCCGGAACCCGACGCGCGCCCAGGAAGCAGCCCCUGAGAGCGCCUGGGACAAACGCCGUGCCCAGUGACCCUGCCGAGGGCUGAUCGGGCACCUGUCGCCGCGGGCAACCCUCGCUAUGUGUUCGAAUCCAACCCAGUCCGCCGAGGUGGCCCCUUCCAGUACCCAGGGGAGUGCUUUCUACAUUGUUCGUGCUGAAUACAUUUUCAUGGAGUGGAAGCAAUUUAUCUUCAGGUGGUUUGUCUCUGUAUCCACUCCUUUAUUCUGCAGUUUGAGUCAGGGAAAGAACAGCUUUUUCCUUGAUCAUCUAUCACUUUACAGAAGUGUACAAUCUUAGCAAAAUGGUGUCAUGUCAUAUUAACCAAUAUUCUCACAAUUGGUGAUACUAAUGAAGACUCUGAGGGAUGAGAAGAUGAUGACAACAUUUUUGAUUCACUAAGAUUAAAUUAUGAUGCUCAAGAUUACCCACGUAUCUUAGGCUAAUGACCUUCAAGCCGGAAGUGCCCUAGGGCGGGAAAAGGUGAACCGGAAGGGCCAACAGGAGCUAGAGGCGCGCUUCGCUGAGGGGCUGCUUUGGCCUGGAGCCUCCUGACUGCUGGGCUGUGUCUAGAAUCUUCCACGCUCCCGACCCAGGAGAAGCAGCCACACUGAGGCAUCCAUCUGGAUCUCUGCUUGGGCAGGAUUGAGACUGCGGGAAAUAAAUAUUAAUAUGGAAAGCAACUUCAAUACUGAGUCAUCAUCUACUUUUACUCUUCAAAGUUCUUCAGAGACAUUGUUUUCUAUUCAGCUAUUAGAUUUCAAAACAAGUUUACUGGAGGCAUUAGAAGAAUUGCGUAUGAGAAGGGAAGCAGAAAUUCAUUAUGAAGAGCAGAUUGGUAAAAUUAUUGUGGAGACACAGGAACUUAAAUGGCAAAAGGAAACUCUUCAGAAUCAAAAGGAAACAUUGGCAGAGCAACACAAGGAAGCAAUGGCAGUUUUUAAAAAGCAGUUGCAGAUGAAGAUGUGUGCCCUGGAAGAAGAAAAGGGAAAAUAUCAACUUGCUACAGAAAUAAAGGAAAAAGAAAUAGAAGGAUUGAAGGAAACAUUAAAAGCACUACAGGUUUCUAAAUACUCUUUACAGAAGAAAGUGAGUGAAAUGGAACAAAAGGUCCAGUUACAUCUUCUGGCUAAAGAAGACUAUCAUAAGCAACUGAGUGAAAUUGAGAAAUAUUAUGCCACAAUAACAGGUCAAUUUGGAUUGGUAAAAGAGAAUCAUGAAAAGUUAGAACAAAAUGUACGGGAAGCAAUACAAUCAAACAAAAGACUUUCAGCUUUAAAUAAAAAACAAGAAGCUGAAAUAUGCAGUUUAAAGAAGGAACUAAAAAAAGCAGCCUCAGACUUGAUAAAGUCCAAAGUCACAUGUCAAUAUAAGAUGGGAGAAGAAAACAUCAAUCUAACAAUUAAAGAACAAAAAUUUCAAGAACUUCAAGAAAGACUCAACAUGGAAUUGGAAUUAAAUGAGAAGAUUAAUGAAGAGAUUACCCAUAUUCAAGAAGAAAAACAGGAUAUCAUCAUUUCUUUCCAACAUAUGCAGCAGUUACUUCGGCAACAAAUUCAAGCUAAUACUGAAAUGGAGGCAGAAUUGAAGGUGCUAAAAGAAAAUAAUCAGACCCUUGAAAGAGAUAAUGAGCUGCAAAGGGAGAAGGUAAAAGAAAAUGAAGAAAAGUUUCUUAAUCUUCAAAAUGAGCAUGAAAAAGCACUAGGAACUUGGAAAAGACAUGCUGAAGAACUUAAUGGAGAAAUUAAUAAGAUUAAAAAUGAAUUAUCAUCCCUUAAAGAAACUCAUAUUAAGUUACAAGAACAUUAUAACAAAUUAUGCAAUCAAAAAACAUUUGAGGAAGACAAAAAGUUUCAGAAUGUUCCAGAAGUAAAUAAUGAAAACAGUGAAAUGUCAACUGAAAAAUCAGAAAACACCAUUAUACAGAAAUAUAAUACUGAGCAAGAAAUAAGGGAAGAAAAUAUGGAGAAUUUUUGUUCAGAUACUGAAUACAGAGAAAAAGAAGAAAAAAAAGAAGGCUCAUUUAUAGAGGAAAUAAUUAUAGAUGAUUUACAGCUUUUUGAAAAAAGCUUCAAGAAUGAAAUUGAUACUGUUGUUUCUCAGGAUGAAAAUCAAAGUGAAAUCUCCUUAAGCAAAACCCUCUCCUUAGAUAAAGAAGUAAUUAGUCAAGGACAAACCUCGAAUGUUACGGACAACAGAAAAUCAGUUACUACAGAAAUAAAAGACAAGAUAUGCUUGGAAAAAGACAAUGGAUGUACAGAAUUUAAAUCACCAAAUAAUCAUUUUGUAGUGUUAGAUACAGCAAUAGAAACAGAAAAAAUACAUCUAGAAAGAACCAGAGGAUUAGAUGUUCACCAUACAGAUGUAAAUCUGGAGGUUGAAAAUAACAAAACAUCAUUUAACAGUAUUUUAAAUGAGACAGCACACAAUACAUAUCACAAUAAUAAUAAAGAUGUUUCUGAAAAUGAGCCAUUCAAACAAUUCAGAUUGCUUCCAGGGACUCGAGAACAUGCUCUAGAGAAGGAAAUUACAAAUAGUGACCAAACCAAAGCAGAUUUGGACUCGUCUCUAGAUAUAAAAAAAAAUCCUGUUCCAUGUCAGAAAUAUAGUUUACGGAAUUCAAGUAAUGUUAUGUUAGAUGAUAAACAAUGUAAAAUAAAACAAAUACAACUGUUAACUAAAAAAAGUGAGUGCAGCAUAUUACUUUCUAAACAAACUUCAGAUUUUCUGCAAGUCUGUAAUGAUACUUUAGAGAAAUCUGAACUAACUGUUCCCUGUGAUAUAGUAAUCGACCACCAUGUUUCAUAUGCUGCUUUUAGUGCUAAUUCAAAACUACUUCUGAAGAACUCAGAUAAAAAUGUCCAUAGUAUGUCUAUGUUGGUGAAACCUAACUCAAGCCCUGGGGGAAAAACUAUGUGUAAAAAUAUGAGUGAUAUGCAAAACAGUCAAUUUAAUAACUGUUUGGGAUACUUAGAAAACACUAAUGUGAACAUUUCCCAUCUUCAUCUUAACAAUGAGAAUAGUCAUGCUUCACAAGCCAAAGAUGUGAAAACUGCUGUUCACAUGAAAACUUGCACAGAAACAGAGUUUUCCAAUAAAAAGAAUCAGAUUGAUGAGAAUCAGGUAACUGAAGCCACAAAAAAUGACCUCUUCCUUUUUGUGAGCAUUAAUGAAAGACAGCAUACAUUGUUAAAUAAUACAGAGAAAACAGAAUCAUUAAAUGACAUUGUUUCAGGAAAAAUGUUCAGUGAAGGACAGCUGGAGGAAUCACAUUCAUUUCACAUAGAGCCAUCUGGAGAUUUAGUAAACAGAAGCGGAAGGUCAACCUUUGAUCUUUCAACUUCAGAUAAAAAAACUGAGAAAACUCCAGUAUACAUGAAUUUUUCAGACCCCGGUCCUUGGUCAAAAGUAAAUCACAUUGAAAGUCAAACAGCGAGCAGUUCGACCCCUUGCAUUUCUUUGUUGCUGAAGGAGAGACCACUAGAUCCAUCAGAAAACAAAAAGAUCAUUUCAAUGGCUCUUUGUAAAAAUAUUGGUGUGGAUGAUGUUGGAAAGGAUAUUGGACCAGAUACUACCAGCAUUAACAGAGUUGCUGACACUUUGAAUAACUGGAGUAUCCAUCCAGAUCCCAAGGGAGAACCCAGUGAAGAGAAGAAUGCAAUGGCAAAGACUUUUUAUGAUUCCUCUUUUCCCACAGAACAUGUGAAAACAAAGCCUCUGAUAUCAACUCCACUACAAAGCCAUUUGCAGGCAAUCAAGACGACUAAAAAUACUUCUGGUGAUGAUGACUGGCAGAGCCUCAUUACGAAUCAACUAAAUAAAAGUGAAAAUUUACUAAGUUUAGAAAAUGACAACCAGCCAAAGAAAAGAAAAGCAGAAGAGACGUUGGAAAAAAACAACAGAUUAAAAUAAUGUAGAUAAGUGCUUUCAGUAGUGAAAUUAUGUAACUGAAAUUCUGGUAUAGUUUUUACUAGAAUAAAAUGACUGUUGUAUUUAAAGCUC